GCGGCAGGCGCUGGACCCCAGGCUGGAUCUUCCAGUGGCUCCCGCGUCCUCCGGGACCGGGUGGCCUGGGGCGGGCGGCCGGUAUUCGGGUGGCUGCUUGGUCUAGGGCCAGUUUCCUGCGCGGCCGGGGCCGGGGGCGUGGCGCGGGUGGCCUGCAGCGCCUCCCCAGGGUGCGCCUUCGCCUCGUCCGUCGGAGAUGCUUUCCCCGCGCGUUUCUCGCGGCGUUGCAGUCCUUACUGUGUGAAAGGCCCCCGCGGCGCUCCCGGCCGCCGUCUUCUUCCCGCGCCCUUGGGCUCGCGUCCUGCCCGUCCGGGCCUGGCGUACGCUGCCGGGAACCCACGCGGCGCUGGCGCCGGGCGCCUUCAAGGGACGCGCUCCCGUCUUUCUCCCGCCCCGGGUUUCUCCGUGAAAAAGCGCUCGGUUUGAUGGCCACUGUCCUAGGUUUCGUGGGAAUAAAGCGCGCAGAGCCCAUGACUCGGGGGCAGGAGAAAGGGAGUCCCGAAAGCGCGAGGCGGAACCGCGGGAGCAGGCCGGCCUCUGCGAGCUUGCUCACUUCCGACAGAGAAAAACAAAAGGUGACAGUUCGCAUUCGGAGAAAAAGACGGCGAAGAGGAAGGGCUCGGCUGUCGAUGCGUCUGUCCAGGAGGAGAGUCCGGUAACCAAGGAGGACAGCGCACUCUGUGGAGGAGGGGACAUUUGCAAAAGCACAUCAUGUGACGACACCCCUGAUGGGGCAGGAGGGGCCUUUGCAGCUCAGCCGGAGGACUGUGAUGGAGAGAAGAGAGAGGACUUGGAACAGCUGCAGCAGAAGCAAGUCAAUGACCAUCCUCCAGAGCAGUGUGGGAUGUUCACAGUCAGUGACCACCCACCAGAACAGCAUGGGAUGUUCACAGUCGGUGACCACCCACCAGAACAGCGUGGGAUGUUCACAGUCAGUGACCACCCACCAGAACAGCAUGGGAUGUUCACAGUCAGUGACCACCCACCAGAACAGCGUGGGAUGUUCACAAUCAGUGACCACCAACCGGAACAGCGUGGGAUGUUCACAGUCAGUGACCACACACCAGAACAGCGUGGGAUCUUCACAAUCAGUGACCACCCAGCAGAACAGCGUGGGAUGUUCACAAAGGAGUGUGAACAAGAAUGUGAACUUGCCAUUACUGACCUGGAGAGCGGCCGUGAAGAUGAGGCUGGCCUGCAUCAGAGUCAGGCCGUGCAUGGCCUUGAGCUGGAGGCGCUGCGCCUGAGUCUGAGCAACAUGCACACGGCGCAGCUGGAGCUGACACAGGCCAACCUCCAGAAGGAGAAGGAGACGGCAUUGACGGAGCUGCGGGAGAUGCUCAACAGCCGGCGUGCCCAGGAGCUGGCCCUGCUACAGAGCAGGCAGCAGCACGAGCUGGAGCUCCUCAGGGAGCAGCACGCACGGGAGAAGGAGGAGGUGGUGCUCAGGUGUGGACAGGAAGCAGCUGAGCUGAAGGAGAAGUUACAAUCAGAAAUGGAGAAAAACGCCCAGAUAGUAAAGACCCUGAAGGAAGAUUGGGAAUCUGAAAAAGAUUUAUGUUUAGAAAAUCUACGCAAAGAACUGUCUGCAAAGCAUCAAUCAGAAAUGGAGGAUUUACAAAACCAGUUUCAGAAAGAAUUGGCAGAACAGAGAGCUGAGUUGGAGAAGAUUUUUCAAGACAAAAACCAGGCUGAACGGGCCCUUAGGAACCUGGAGAGUCAUCAUCAAGCAGCCAUUGAGAAGUUACGUGAAGACCUGCAGUCCGAGCACGGCCGGUGUUUAGAAGACUUGGAGUUCAAGUUCAAAGAGAGCGAGAAAGAAAAACAGCUGGAGUUAGAGAAUCUUCAAGCAUCAUAUGAAGACCUGAAGGCACAAUCACAAGAAGAGAUCAGGCGCUUGUGGUCCCAGCUUGAUUCUGCCAGGACCAGUAGACAGGAAUUGAGUGAGCUACAUGAGCAACUCCUGGCGCGCACCUCUCGUGUGGAAGAUUUAGAACAGCUGAAGCAGCGAGAAAAAACCCAGCAUGAGUCCGAACUGGAGCAACUGAGGAUUUAUUUUGAAAAGAAGUUAAGGGAUGCUGAGAAAACUUACCAAGAAGACCUAACCCUGUUACAGCAGAGGCUGCAGGGGGCGAGGGAAGAUGCUCUUCUGGACUCUGUGGAAGUUGGGUUGUCCUGUGUGGGUUUAGAAGAGAAACCUGAGAAAGGAAGAAAAGAUCACGUUGAUGAACUCGAGCCUGAGCGACAUAAGGAGAGCCUGCCACGCUUCCAGGCGGAGUUAGAAGAAAGCCACAGGCACCAGCUGGAAGCGCUGGAGUCUCCCCUCUGCAUCCAGCACGAGGGGCAUGUCUCAGACAGAUGCUGCGUAGAGACUUCAGCAUUGGGACACGAGUGGCGUCUGGAACCCUCUGAAGGGCACAGCCAAGAGCUUCCCUGGGUGCAUCUCCAGGGUGUGCAGGACGGGGACUUGGAGGCCGACACAGAGCGGGCAGCCAGAGUCUUGGGUCUGGAAACUGAGCACAAGGUGCAACUUUCGCUUCUUCAGACUGAGCUCAAAGAAGAAAUUGAACUCCUAAAAAUAGAAAAUAGAAAUUUGUAUGGGAAGUUGCAGCAUGAAACUCGUCUGAAGGACGAUUUGGAGAAGGUAAAACACAAUCUAAUUGAAGACCACCAGAAGGAACUAAAUAAUGCUAAGCAAAAGACUGAGCUGAUGAAACAGGAAUUCCAAAGAAAAGAAACGGACUGGAAAGUUAUGAAGGAGGAGCUACAGCGGGAAGCUGAGGAGAAGUUAACAUUGAUGCUACUUGAACUGAGAGAAAAGGCUGAAUCCGAGAAACAGACCAUCAUAAACAAGUUUGAGCUUCGAGAAGCUGAAAUGAGGCAGCUUCAGGACCAACAGGCAGCCCAGAUCCUGGAUCUGGAGAGGUCCUUGACGGAGCAGCAGGGCCGCCUGCAGCAGCUGGAACAGGACCUCACUUCAGACGACGCCCUGCAUUGCAGCCAGUGUGGGCGGGAGCCGCCCACAGCCCAGGACGGGGAGCUUGCUGCGCUCCACGUGAAGGAAGACUGCGCCCUGCAGCUGAUGCUGGCCCGGAGCAGGUUUUUAGAGGAACGUAAAGAGAUCACCGAGAAAUUCAGUGCGGAACAAGAUGCCUUCCUGCAGGAGGCCCAGGAGCAGCAUGCCCGUGAGCUGCAGCUCCUCCAGGAGAGACACCAGCAGCAGCUCCUGUCAGUGACGGCGGAGCUCGAGGCCAGACACCAGGCCGCGUUGGGCGAGCUGACAGCCUCCUUAGAGAGCAAGCAGGGGGCUCUGCUGGCUGCACGUGUGGCCGAACUGCAGACAAAACACGCUGCCGACCUCGGCGCUCUGGAGACCAGACAUCUGUCCAGCCUUGAUUCUUUGGAAUCCUGUUACCUCUCUGAAUUUCAGACCAUCCGUGAGGAGCACAGGCAGGCCCUAGAGCUCUUACGAGCAGACUUUGAGGAACAACUGUGGAAAAAGGACUCUCUUCACCAAACGAUUUUGACUCAAGAGUUGGAGAAACUGAAGCGGAAACACGAAGGGGAGCUACAGUCUGUGCGGGACCACCUGCGAACCGAAGUGAGCACAGAGCUCGCCGGAACCGUGGCUCACGAGCUGCAGGGAGUGCACCAGGGUGAAUUUGGAAGUGAAAAGAAAACUGCUUUGCAUGAAAAAGAGGAGACACUUCGGCUUCAGAGUGCACAGGCACAGCCUUUUCACCAAGAGGAGAAAGAGUCUUUGUCUCUGCAGCUUCAAAAGAAGAAUCACCAAGUCCAGCAGCUGAAAGACCAGGUUUUAUCCUUAAGUCACGAGAUAGAAGAGUGCCGCUCCGAGUUGGAGGUGCUGCAGCAGAGGCGGGAGCGGGAGAACCGGGAAGGCGCAAACCUCCUCUCCAUGCUCAAGGCCGACGUCAACCUGUCCCACAGCGAAAGAGGGGCCCUCCAGGACGCCCUGCGCAGGCUGCUGGGUUUGUUUGGAGAGACGCUGAGGGCAGCCGUCACCCUGAGGAGCCGGAUCGGGGAGCGCGUGGGGCUCUGCCUGGAUGACGCGGGCGCAGGCCUGGCCCUGUCGACAGCUCCGGCGCUGGAGGAGACAUGGUCUGAUGUGGCCCUCCCGGAGUUGGACAGAACUUUGUCUGAAUGUGCAGAGAUGUCUUCCGUGGCUGAAAUUAGCAGCCACAUGCGUGAAAGCUUUCUCAUGAGCCCAGAAAGUGUGCGGGAGUGUGAGCAGCCCAUCCGGAGGGUCUUCCAGAGCCUCAGCCUGGCCGUGGACGGCCUCAUGGAGAUGGCCCUGGACUCCAGCAGGCAGCUGGAAGAAGCACGCCAAAUUCAUUCUCGUUUUGAAAAAGAAUUUAGUUUUAAGAAUGAGGAGACAGCACAGGUUGUCAGGAAGCACCAGGAGCUGCUGGAGUGUUUGAAGGAGGAGAGCGCAGCAAAGGCAGAGCUGGCGCUGGAGCUGCACAAGACUCAGGGUACCCUUGAGGGAUUCAAGGUGGAGACAGCAGAUCUGAAGGAGGUGCUGGCCGGGAAGGAGGAUUCCGAGCACCGUCUGGUGCUGGAGCUGGAGAGCCUGAGACGGCAGCUGCAGCAGGCGGCCCAGGAGCAGGCGGCGCUGAGGGAGGAGUGCACCCGUCUGUGGAGUCGGGGGGAGGCCACAGCCACGGACGCCGAGGCCAGAGAAGCUGCUCUCCGGAAGGAAGUGGAGGAUCUGACCAAAGAACAGUCGGAGACCAGGAAGCAGGCUGAGAAGGACCGCUCAGCCCUGCUCUCCCAGAUGAAGAUUUUGGAGUCUGAGUUAGAAGAACAGCUGUCUCAGCAUCGCGGGUGUGCCAAGCAGGCGGAGGCCGUCACUGCCCUGGAACAGCAGGUGGCAUCUCUGGACAAGCAUUUGCGCAACCAGCGGCAAUUCAUGGAUGAGCAGGCAGCCGAGCGGGAGCACGAGCGCGAGGAGUUCCAGCAGGAGAUUCAGAGGCUGGAGGGGCAGCUCCGCCAGGCGGCCAAGCCGCAGCCCUGGGGCCCUCGCGACAGCCAGCAGGCGCCGCUGGAUGGAGAGGUUGAGUUGUUACAACAAAAGUUGAGAGAAAAGUUGGAUGAAUUUAAUGAAUUGGCUAUACAGAAAGAGUCGGCAGAUAGACAAGUGUUAAUGCAGGAAGAAGAAAUUAAACGUCUGGAGGAGAUGAACAUCAACAUCAGGAAAAAAGUGGCCCAGCUCCAGGAAGAAGUGGAAAAACAGAAAAACAUCGUGAAAGGGCUGGAACAGGAUAAAGAGGUGUUAAAGAAACAGCAGAUGAGUAGCUUGCUUCUGGCGUCCACGUUGCAGUCUACACUAGAUGCAGGCAGAUGUCCCGAGCCUCCUUCGGGCAGCCCUCCUGAGGGUCCAGAAAUACAGUUAGAGGUGACACAGAGAGCACUCCUGCGGCGCGAGAGCGAGGUUUUGGACUUAAAAGAACAGCUAGAAAAGAUGAAAGGUGACUUAGAAAGUAAAAAUGAAGAAAUACUACAUCUGAACUUAAAAUUGGACAUGCAGAACAGCCAGACUGCUGUCAGCCUCAGAGAACUUGAGGAAGAGAACACGAGCUUGAAGGUCAUAUAUACCAGAAGUUCUGAGAUUGAAGAGCUGAAAGCCACUAUUGAAAAUCUGCAAGAGAAUCAGAAACGAUUACAAAAGGAGAAAGCAGAGGAAAUUGAACAACUCCAUGAAGUCAUUGAGAAGCUGCAGCACGAGCUGUCCCUCAUGGGGCCUGUGGUGCACGAAGUCAGCGACAGUCAGGCUGGCAGUCUGCAGAGCGAGCUGCUCUGCUCCCAGGCCGGGGGCCCUCGUGGGCAGGCCCUACAGGGCGAGCUCGAGGCUGCGCUGGAAGCCAAGGAGGCCCUGAGCCGGCUGCUGGCUGACCAGGAGCGCAGGCACAGCCAGGCCCUGGAGGCCCUGCAGCAGCGCCUCCAGGGCGCAGAGGAGGCUGCGGAGCUACAGCUGGCUGAGCUGGAGCGCAAUGUAGCCCUCAGGGAGGCUGAGGUCGAAGACAUGGCCUCCCGGAUCCAGGAGUUCGAAGCGGCCCUGAAAGCAAAGGAAGCGACGAUUGCCGAGAGAAAUUUAGAAAUCGACGCUCUGAACCAGCGGAAGGCGGCCCACUCUGCCGAGCUGGAGGCCGUCCUGUUGGCCUUGGCCCGCAUCCGCCGCGCCCUGGAGCAGCAGCCCCUGGCAGCCGGGGCGGCGCCUCCCGAGCUGCAGUGGCUCCGAGCGCAGUGUGCCCGCCUCAGCCGCCAGCUGCAGGUGCUGCACCAGCGGUUCCUGAGGUGCCAGGUGGAGCUGGACAGGCGGCAGGCCCGCAGAGCCACAGCUCACACACGGGUGCCCGGGGCCCACCCACAGCCUCGCAUGGAUGGUGGCGCCAAGGCCCAGGUCACCGGCGACGUGGAGGCCUCCCAUGAUGCUGCUUUGGAGCCGGUUGUCCCUGACCCACAGGGUGAUCUGCAGCCUGUCCUGGUGACGUUGAAGGAUGCACCUCUCUGCAAGCAAGAAGGCGUGAUGUCAGUGCUCACCGUCUGCCAGAGGCAGCUGCAGUCGGAGCUGCUCUUGGUGAAAAAUGAAAUGCGCCUGAGUCUGGAGGACGGCGGCAAGGGUAAAGAAAAAGUACUGGAAGAUUGUCAGCUGCCGAAGGUCGAUCUCGUAGCUCAGGUGAAACAGCUUCAGGAAAAACUGAACCGUUUGCUGUAUUCCAUGACCUUCCAGAAUGUGGAUGCUGCCGACACCAAAUCUCUGUGGCCCAUGGCCUCAGCACACCUGUUGGAGAGCAGCUGGAGUGAUGAUUCCUGUGACGGAGAAGAGCCUGACAUAUCACCCCACAUAGACACAUGUGAUGCCAAUACAGCCACGGGGGGUGUAACUGAUGUUAUCAAAAAUCAGGCCAUAGACGCGUGUGAUGCCAAUACAACCCCAGGGGGUGUAACUGAUGUUAUCAAAAAUUGGGAUUCCUUGAUACCAGAUGAAAUGCCAGAUUCUCCCAUUCAAGAAAAAUCAGAAUGUCAGGACAUGUCUCUUUCUUCACCGACCAGCGUACUUGGUGGCUCCCGCCACCAGAGCCACACUGCAGAGGCUGGGCCCCGGAAGAGCCCGGUCGGGAUGCUGGACCUGUCUUCCUGGAGCUCCCCUGAGGUCCUCAGGAAGGACUGGACCCUGGAGCCCUGGCCCAGCCUCCCCGUGACACCCCACUCAGGAGCCCUGAGCCUGUGCAGUGCCGACACAUCCCUGGGGGACAGGGCGGACACCUCGCUGCCACAGACCCAGGGGCCGGGGCUGCUUUGUUCCCCAGGCGUGUCUGCAGCAGCGCUGGCACUGCAGUGGGCCGAGUCUCCGCCGGCUGACGACCACCAUGUGCAGAGGACGGCUGUGGAGAAAGAUGUCGAAGAUUUUAUCACAACAUCCUUUGAUUCUCAAGAAACAUUAAGUUCACCUCCUCCUGGAUUAGAAGGAAAAGCUGAUAGAAGUGAGAAAAGUGACGGCUCGGGUUUUGGAGCAAGACUGAGCCCGGGGUCAGGAGGCCCUGAGGCUCAAACUGCUGGUCCUGUGACCCCUGCUUCCAUCUCUGGAAGGUUUCAGCCGCUGCCGGAAGCCAUGAAGGAGAAGGAAGUGCGUCCGAAGCACGUGAAGGCUUUACUGCAGAUGGUGCGUGACGAGAGCCACCAGAUCCUGGCGCUGUCAGAAGGCCUUGCACCCCCAAGCGGCGAGCCACACCCACCCCGGAAGGAAGACGAGAUACAGGACAUCUCGCUCCAUGGGGGAAAGACGCAGGAAGUGCCCACCGCGUGCCCCGAUUGGAGAGGGGACCUUCUGCAGGUUGUGCAAGAGGCCUUUGAAAAAGAGCAGGAGAUGCAGGGGGUUGAGCUGCAGCCCCGACUCAGUGGCUCAGAUCUGGGGGGUCACAGCUCCCUGCUCGAAAGGCUGGAGAAGAUCAUCCGUGAGCAGGGAGACCUGCAGGAAAAGUCCCUGGAGCAUCUUCGCUUGCCGGACCGGAGCAGCCUGCUGUCCGAGAUCCAGGCGCUGCGUGCCCAGCUGCGCAUGACGCACCUGCAGAACCAGGAGAAGCUGCAGCACUUGCGCACGGCGCUGACAAGCGCAGAGGCGCGCGGGAGCCAGCAGGAGCACCAGCUGCGCAGGCAGGUUGAACUGCUGGCUUAUAAAGUAGAGCAGGAGAAGUGCAUUGCUGGUGACUUGCAGAAGACGCUGAGUGAAGAGCAAGAGAAGGCAAACAGCGUGCAGAAGCUCCUGGCGGCGGAGCAGACUGUAGUGCGAGAUUUGAAGUCCGACCUCUGUGAGAGCAGGCAGAAGAGCGAACAGCUGUCCCGGUCCCUCUGCGAGGUGCAGCAGGAGGUCCUCCAGCUGAGAUCCAUGCUGAGCAGUAAGGAGAACGAGCUGAAGGCCGCGCUUCAGGAGCUGGAGAGUGAGCAGGGGAAGGGGCGUGCCCUGCAGAGCCAGCUGGAGGAGGAGCAGCUGCGGCACCUGCAGAGGGAGAGCCAGAGUGCCAAGGCCCUGGAGGAGCUGCGGGCGUCUUUGGAGACACAGCGUGCUCAGAGCAGUCGACUCUGCGUGGCACUGAAACACGAGCAGACGGCCAAGGACAACCUGCAGAAGGAGCUGCGUAUCGAGCACUCACGCUGCGAGGCCUUGCUGGCUCAGGAGCGGAGCCAGCUCUCUGAGCUCCAGAAGGACCUUGCGGCUGAGAAGAGCCGCACCCUGGAGCUGUCAGAGGCCUUGCGGCACGAGCGGCUCCUGACCGAGCAGCUGAGCCAGAGGACACAGGAGGCUUGCGUGCACCAGGACACACAGGCCCAUCACGCUCUGCUGCAGAAGCUGAAGGAGGAGAAGUCCCGGGUGGUGGACUUGCAAGCGAUGCUUGAAAAGGUGCAGCAGCAAGCCCUGCAUUCUCAGCAGCAGCUUGAGGCUGAGGCUCAGAAGCACUGUGAGGCGCUCAGGAGAGAGAAGGAGCGAGAAUUAGAACUGCAGCGUCAGCGUGACUUGCAUAAGAUCAAGCAGCUUCAGCAGACAGUGAGAGACCUGGAGUCGAAGGACGAGGUGCCUGGCAGCCGCCUCCACCUAGGUUCUGCCCGCAGGGCUGCCGGCUCGGAUGCGGACCACCUCCGGGAACAGCAGCGAGAGCUGGAGGCGAUGAGGCAGCGGCUGCUCUCUGCCGCCCGGCUUCUCACCAGCUUCACCAGCCAGGCCGUGGACAGGACAGUUAAUGAUUGGACGUCAUCCAAUGAGAAAGCAGUGAUGUCUUUACUGCACACGUUGGAGGAGCUGAAGUCUGACUUGAGCAGGCCCACCUCCUCCCAGAAAAAAAUGGCAGCAGAGCUGCAGUUCCAGUUUGUGGACGUCCUGCUGAAAGACAAUGUUUCCCUCACAAAAGCGCUCAGCACGGUGACCCAGGAGAAGCUGGAGCUGAGCAGAGCCGUGUCUAAGCUUGAGAAGUUGCUGAAGCACCAUCUGCAGAAGGGCUGCAGCCCAAGCAGGUCGGAAAGGUCUGCUUGGAAGCCAGACGAAACGGCUCCACAGAGUUCCCUGAGGCGCCCAGACCCCGGCCGGCUUCCACCAGCUGCCAGCGAGGAAGCACACACCAGCAAUGUCAAGAUGGAAAAAUUGUACCUGCAUUACUUGAGAGCAGAGAGCUUUAGAAAAGCUCUGAUUUAUCAAAAGAAGUAUCUUUUGCUGUUGAUUGGUGGAUUCCAGGAUUCUGAACAAGAAACACUCUCCAUGAUUGCCCAUUUGGGGGUAUUUCCUUCCAAAGCAGAACGGAAAAUCACAUCUCGUCCUUUCACCAGGUUCCGCACGGCCGUCAGGGUGGUCAUUGCAAUAUUAAGAUUACGUUUUUUGGUUAAGAAAUGGCAAGAAGUAGAUCGGAAAGGAGCUCUGGCACAAGGCAAAGCCCCUCGCCCAGGGCCCCGAGCACGACAGCCGCAGUCUCCACCCAGAACCAGAGAGUCCCCCCCAACCCGGGAUGUACCCUCUGGCCACACCAGGGACCCUGCCAGAGGCCGCAGACUGGCAGCAGCAGCCUCCCCACACAGUGGGGGAAGAGCCACUCCAUCCCCAAAUUCAAGAUUAGAAAGAUCCCUGACUGCUUCUCAAGAUCCAGAACAUUCCUUGACAGAGUAUAUUCACCAUUUAGAAGUGAUCCAGCAAAGAUUGGGAGGGGUACUACCAGAUUCUACUUCAAAGAAAUCCUGCCACCCGAUGAUUAAACAGUGAAUAAAAUGUCAUGGCUCUUUCCUGCGACAAUUCUAUUUGAGGAAAAGAUUUGUUUUUCCCUUUUCCCAAGGAAGCUCGUGGGACAGCAUGGGCACUACUCUUCAUGUGCGGUGACACCAGCCCCCAGAUGCCUUGAAUUAAGUGUCCUCACCUUUAUGCAUGACUGCAAAGCCAGCUGGAGCAUUUUCUAUGGAGCCUCCGUAUGUUUUAGGCCCAUGACCUUCGUGAGGUGACGGGCACUCACUCCCAUGAGCCCUGGCUGUGUGCUGUUGUGUGCCUAUCGGCAGAUCCAUCCUUCCUGCCUCCAAGGAGGAUACACAGAGAAUGGCUUCCUGUUGUUUUGUUUAUUUUCUUAACGUGUACAGAUGGAAACUUCAUUUAAAAAUAAAAACAAAACAACUCAAAAAGGAAUAAAAUUUAAUCACUGUUUUGUUUGUGAAUA